ACCGCCUACGUCGGGCUGCGUGACAAUGGGGCCGGCGGCAGAACGCAGCUGCGGCGGCUGCGGGUCUCGUGGGGGCGGAGCGGUCGCCGCUGCCGCCGCAGCUCGGGUCGGGAUUUGAAAGAUUAGAAACUUCGGGUGGAGAGGGCGGCGGCGUUGAAUGUGUGGCGGAAGCGCUGGGGGUCACGGCUCCGCGCGCCGCCGGACAGCCGGCGGCGUCUCCACAGCAUGAAUUACCCGGGCCGCGGGUCCCCACGGAGCCCCGAGCAUAACGGCCGAGGCGGCGGCGGCGGCGCCUGGGAGCUGGGCUCAGACGCGAGGCCAGCGUUCGGCGGCGGCGUCUGCUGCUUCGAGCACCUGCCCGGCGGGGACCCGGACGACGGCGACGUGCCCCUGGCCCUGCUGCGCGGGGAACCCGGGCUGCAUUUGGCGCCGGGCACCGACGACCACAACCACCACCUCGCGCUGGACCCCUGCCUCAGUGACGAGAACUAUGACUUCAGCUCCGCCGAGUCGGGCUCCUCGCUGCGCUACUACAGCGAGGGUGAGAGCGGCGGCGGCGGCAGCUCCUUGUCGCUGCACCCGCCGCAGCAGCCUCCGCUGGUCCCGACGAACUCGGGGGGCGGCGGCGCGACAGGAGGGUCCCCCGGGGAAAGGAAACGUACCCGGCUUGGCGGCCCGGCGGCCCGGCACCGCUAUGAGGUAGUGACGGAGCUGGGCCCGGAGGAGGUACGCUGGUUCUACAAGGAGGACAAGAAGACCUGGAAGCCCUUCAUCGGCUACGACUCGCUCCGCAUCGAGCUCGCCUUCCGGACCCUGCUGCAGACCACGGGUGCCCGGCCCCAGGGCGGGGACCGGGACGGCGACCAUGUGUGCUCCCCCACGGGCCCAGCCUCCAGUUCCGGAGAAGAUGACGAUGAGGACCGCGCCUGCGGCUUCUGCCAGAGUACGACGGGGCACGAGCCGGAGAUGGUGGAGCUUGUGAACAUCGAGCCUGUGUGCGUGCGGGGCGGCCUCUACGAGGUGGAUGUGACCCAAGGAGAGUGCUACCCGGUGUACUGGAACCAGGCUGAUAAAAUACCAGUAAUGCGUGGACAGUGGUUUAUUGACGGCACUUGGCAGCCUCUAGAAGAGGAAGAAAGUAAUUUAAUUGAGCAAGAACAUCUCAAUUGUUUUAGGGGCCAGCAGAUGCAGGAAAAUUUCGAUAUUGAAGUGUCAAAAUCCAUAGAUGGAAAAGAUGGCAGUGGGAUCAACUAUUCUGUUGUCUACCACCUCCCUCCCUUCUCCCUCCCUUCUCUGUUCAAAUGGAGAAGAUAUAAGGAGAGUACAGAUGCGACAGGUCUUAAACGAAAGCAUUCCCAAGCUGUUCAUAGUUUCAAGUUGAGUCGAAACCAUGUGGACUGGCACAGUGUGGAUGAAGUAUAUCUUUAUAGUGAUGCAACAACAUCUAAAAUUGCAAGAACAGUUACCCAAAAACUGGGAUUUUCUAAAGCAUCAAGUAGUGGUACCAGACUUCAUAGAGGUUAUGUAGAAGAAGCCACAUUAGAAGACAAGCCAUCACAGACUACCCAUAUUGUAUUUGUUGUGCAUGGCAUUGGGCAGAAAAUGGACCAAGGAAGAAUUAUCAAAAAUACAGCUAUGAUGAGAGAAGCUGCAAGAAAAAUAGAAGAAAGGCAUUUUUCCAACCAUGCAACACAUGUUGAAUUUCUGCCUGUUGAGUGGCGGUCAAAACUUACUCUUGAUGGAGACACUGUUGAUUCCAUUACUCCUGACAAAGUACGAGGUUUAAGGGAUAUGCUGAACAGCAGUGCAAUGGACAUAAUGUAUUAUACUAGUCCACUUUAUAGAGAUGAACUAGUUAAAGGCCUUCAGCAAGAGCUGAAUCGAUUGUAUUCCCUUUUCUGUUCUCGGAAUCCAGACUUUGAAGAAAAAGGGGGUAAAGUCUCAAUAGUAUCACAUUCCUUGGGAUGUGUAAUUACUUAUGACAUAAUGACUGGCUGGAAUCCAGUUCGGCUGUAUGAACAGUUGCUGCAAAAGGAAGAAGAGUUGCCUGAUGAACGAUGGAUGAGCUAUGAAGAACGACAUCUUCUUGAUGAACUCUAUAUAACUAAACGACGGCUGAAGGAAAUAGAAGAACGGCUUCACGGAUUGAAAGCAUCAUCUAUGACACAAACACCUGCCUUAAAAUUUAAGGUUGAGAAUUUCUUCUGUAUGGGAUCCCCAUUAGCAGUUUUCUUGGCGUUGCGUGGCAUCCGCCCAGGAAAUACUGGAAGUCAAGACCAUAUUUUGCCUAGAGAGAUUUGUAACCGGUUACUAAAUAUUUUUCAUCCUACAGAUCCAGUGGCUUAUAGAUUAGAACCAUUAAUACUGAAACACUACAGCAACAUUUCACCUGUCCAGAUCCACUGGUACAAUACUUCAAAUCCUUUACCUUAUGAACAUAUGAAGCCAAGCUUUCUCAACCCAGCUAAAGAACCUACCUCAGUUUCAGAGAAUGAAGGCAUUUCAACCAUACCAAGCCCUGUGACCUCACCAGUUUUGUCCCGCCGACACUAUGGAGAAUCUAUAACAAAUAUAGGCAAAGCAAGCAUAUUAGGGGCUGCUAGCAUUGGAAAGGGACUUGGAGGAAUGUUGUUCUCAAGAUUUGGACGUUCAUCUACAACACAGUCAUCUGAAACAUCAAAAGACUCAAUGGAAGAUGAGAAGAAGCCAGUUGCCUCACCUUCUGCUACCACCGUAGGGACACAGACCCUUCCACAUAGCAGUUCUGGCUUCCUCGAUUCUGCAUAUUUCAGACUUCAAGAAUCGUUCUUUAAUCUCCCACAACUUCUUUUUCCGGAAAAUGUAAUGCAGAAUAAAGAUAAUGCCCUCGUGGAGUUGGAUCACAGGAUUGAUUUUGAACUCAGAGAAGGCCUUGUGGAGAGCCGCUAUUGGUCAGCUGUCACGUCGCAUACUGCCUAUUGGUCAUCCUUGGAUGUUGCCCUUUUUCUUUUAACCUUCAUGUAUAAACAUGAGCACGAUGAUGAUGCAAAACCCAAUUUAGAUCCAAUCUGAACUCUCUUGAAGGACAUGAAUGGCCUAAAACUGAUUUUUUUUUUUUCCGUUAAAAUGUGUGUGUCAAGAUACGGAGAUUUCAGGGUUAAAGUAUAUUUCAGUUUUCUUUAGGGCAACAUAUAUUUGAAUUUAAAAGCACUUUAUUUAAAAAAAAAAGAAGUUUUCAGUUCUGAAGAAGUCAUUUACAGUUUGCAUCAUUUUAAUUAUGAGUCUGACAAAACCUUCUCCAGAGAAUCAAGCAAGACCUGGAUGUGAAGAAGGUUUGGGUAAACUGCAUGUAAAGGCUACAAAUCACAAUCUGAUUCCUCCCAAAUAUAAAGGCAUAUGGAACAUAAUGUAUUAACCAAAGUAUGUUAUAAAUCAAAAAUGGUCAAGGUUCAGCAUAUUCUAUAUGAAGAUCACAAGGUGGUAUCGUUUUAGAUUUCUAUGAAGGCUUUCAUUUGUACAUCCCUUUGAAAAAAUAUAACAGAUUUAAAAUGUUUUGAAUUUAACUUGUUUAGAAAAACUAAUGCUUAAAACAAUAUUUGAACUACUGUAUUUAUAAUUUAUUACCUCUAAUUGCUUUAUUUCAGUGUAUGAGACAUUACUGUUUUAAUGUUUGCUUUGAACAUAAUUUAAGAACCAGAUUUAUUUUCUAUAGUGAUAAACCCUUUUUUCUCAGAACUCCAUCUUUGUACUCUUCAGAUGAAUAUAUAGACACUGUGGCAUACAUUUUUUUUCAUUAAAAACUUAUGGCUUCAUACAACACUAGUUCAAUUUUUUAAAUAAACUUUUUAUUAUGUUACAUGUACUUCAGAGAAAGCUAAAGUUUCUCUAAACUUGACACGGAGUACUCCAUAAUGGGUACAUUUCAUUAGCUUUAUUAGAAAACUAGUAAAUGCUUUUGAAUAGGUAGUAUGACAGCUAUUUUAAAUGUAUAAACAUUUGUGUGCCAAACAACAUAUAUGAAGGGAUGUGAUGCCACUAACUAGUGCACAUUGUUUCUCAAUGUGCCAUUGAGACACAAGGCACAGUAAGUCAGGAUUCUGAGGCAUUGGAAGGGUUUUCUUCAGCUGUAAUUGUUUCCACAGUGCUUUUCAUCUGAGGGGCUCAAAGUUUAAGAGUGCAUUCAAUAACCCAUGUACUAGCUUCUUGAGGUAAGUAAAUAAAUCUUGUUCUCAUGUUACAUGUUAAUACACCAAGGCACCAAAACAUUUAAAGUGCCAUGAAUUAGAUUACAUCAGAAAUCAGAAAAGCUUGGAUUGAGCUAGUCACCGUGGUUCACGCCUGUAAUCCCAACACUUCGGGAGGCCAAGAUGGGAGGAUCUCUUGAGCCCAGGAUUUCAAGACCAGCUUGGGCAACAUAGUGAGACCCUCUUCUCUGCAAAAACUGACAAAAAUUAGCCACUUGUAGUGGUGUACACCUGUAGUCCCAGCUACUCAAGAGGCUGAGGUGGGAGGAUCACCCGAGCCCAGAAGUUCAAAGCUGCAGUGAGCUCUGAUCACACCAAUGCACUCCAGCCUGGGUGACAGAGCCAGACCCUGUCUCUAAAAAACAAAAAAGAAAAGCUUGGGUUGAAGCCAGGCCAUAUUCUUUUAUAUGCUGUUCAAUGACUUGAUUCACAUGUGACCUUUUAGUAGUUUGCAAACAAUAAUAACAGAAGUUGCAAUUCAUAAUUCAGAGAAAUGACCAUGAAGCCGGUGUUUCCCUGCUUGAUUUCUAUGUUCUUGGAUUCUCACACAAAAGAGGAGUUACCUAGAGGGGAUCAGUAGCCAUCCCUGUUGCACACAACCCUCACUUCUGAGUGGUUUCCACUAGGUUCCACUUAAGGUGCUGUCUUUUCUUAACUUGCAAGGAAUUGCUUAGCUUCCCAAUAAUCAUUGUCAAACUGGGAGCAAAGUUGGUCAGCUGUAUCUCUCACCUCCUCCUUUCUUCAUAAGAUAGUAGAAUCUGUGGCUUACUUGUAGGUUUUACUUAGUGCUUCAGUACUGUUGGCUGUUUUGGCCUUUUGCUGAAUUUGCACAACAACAUAAAGCACUUCUUUUUAAUGUUUAAAAAAAAUUCCAAGGCUCCAUGACCAAGUAUGUGACUCACUAAGAAACCCUUGCUAUAAAAGGCUUUUGAUGAAAUCUUAGCAAAGCUAAAUUAUCUCUAACUUAGAGAUUCCUAUGAACUCAGGUCAUUUUCAUAGCCUGUUUAUUUUGUAGGUCUAAUUUAGUUCUCAGGAAAAUUAAACUCAUGCUAUAUGACUGUAUCGUUAAAGGUACUUGAGCGUAUGUUGCUGUAGGUGGUAUGACACUCAAAUGCAUAAGAACUUGAAGGGAUUUAUUCUUAACCACUAGAAUAUGAAGAGCCCUUUUUACCUGAGAAGAGUGAAAUUAUGUCAGACCUUUUAAUUUGAUAUCACUGAGUAAAAGGUAUGUUCCUAUAGCCAUAGGAAUAUGUCUGCUUCCUUUUUUUCAUGUUGAGAAAACAGUCAAAUUUAACCAUUUGGAGUUUAUUUGAAUUCUUGGAAAGAGCAAUAUUCAAAACCUUUUCAAAAAUAAGAUAUUCUGGACUACUGGAUGGAUGUUUUGUUUUCAGUUCAUUUUUCAUCAGUAGAGAUGGUGAUUUCGGUUUUGUAGUAUCCUUGUUUCUAUGUCUGUGCAUGUUAACAUUGGAUGUAUUUGUAUAUACUUAAUUAAUAUACAGACUGUGUGUCAUUCUGGCUUGAUUAGAAGCUAAGUCAGUUACUGAGUAACAUUUUGCAACUUUAUUCCAGCAAGUACUAAAUCGGCCAAAAAAAGUUUUGUUUUUGAUACCAUUAAAAUUUUAUUCUCUAUUUUGUGUACAUGCUAUGAUGAUUCUCCCAAGUACUGAUUAGAUCACUGAACUUUAGUUAGCUUCCCAAGAAUUAUUAACCGUUAGAAUAAGACUUAGAUUAAAUCUUGCUUUAUUUUUACUUUAAAAUUAGUCUUGCUAAGGCCUUAUGUUAGUUCAUACUUUCUUUUCAACAGUAAUCUUGUUUAUAAUCCAGUGUUUCUGUGUUUUAGGACAUAAUUUAAAAAUAUACUGGAUUUUGGCCAGGUGUGGCAGCUCAUGCCUGUAAUCCCAGCACUUUGGGAGGCCAAGCAGGGAAGAUUACUUGAGCCCAAGAGUUGAAAACCAACCUGGACAACAUGGUGAAACCCAGACUCUACAAAAAAUGCAAAGAUUAGCUGGGUGUGUUGGCAGACGCCUGUGGUCCCAGCUACUCAGGAGGCUGAGGUCGGUAGGACUGCAUGAUUCCGGGAGGUCAAGGCUUCAGUGAGCCAAGAUUGCACCACUGCACUCCACCUUGGGUGACAGAGCUGGACACUGUAUCCAAAAAAAAAAAGUAUGUAUUUACACACACACACACACACACACACACACACUGGAUGUUCUAAUAACUGCUCUUUUGUAUGUGAAGCAAGCCUUAGGAAUCUUACGUUUUACUUCUUUCUGUUAAACGGCAUCUGUUAUCUUUUGAAGUACUCACACUGAACAUGCUUCAUGCUGAAUACUCACGCUAAAGGCCUCAGACAUGUAAACAUUCAUCCUUAGUCUCUUUUUUCUCUGUUUUCUCAUUGGGAGCUGAAGCAUCCUAGUCUGCAGAAAAUUUAACACACCAUAUUCCAGCUUUGCAUCACCUAGACAGUAGACAAAAGGAAAAGAAAUUGUCAGUACCGUAUCACAGCUAGUGCCUCUGUUCAUUCCAGUGAUAGUACAUGAGCCCCUUCCAGUGGAGUCAGAUCAAGCCAAAAGAUUUUCCUGUAAAGUCUGUAGUAGAAGACAAAUUUCUUUUUGAUCCAUUAGAUUGGUAUUUCUAUCUUCUCAGCUAAUUAAUGAGUAAGGCAUGUGGACAAUCGAGAAAACUAAUUUGAGUGUAUGUAUUAAAAUUGCUCUUCUAAAAACACGUAAAAUAUUAAAGAUCAAGGCAGAGCAAAAAAGAACGUAGCAAUCAUAUACUAGAAAAAGAAACUAAGUUUUGCUAAACUAUGUUUGGGUUAGUUGACCUCUGUAGCUAUUCUAAAGUUUUCUAUCCCUUAUCUGUAUUCCGCUGUCAUUCCUGUGCCUCAAGCCUCUGCCAGGAAUCUGAUGGUACUCUGGCUGAACUUAAAACAUAAGAAUCUCAAAGGUCUCAUUUAGUAAAUGUUAGUGCUAAGUUGGUGACAGCCUGGGUUAUAUGCUUUCUCUUUCAGUCUUCAGUAGAUGCUUGUGAUAGUUUUCAAAGAACUGUAAAAUUUCCGGGUCUGUACAGAUUUUUAGAGAUCAUUUAAUCCAACCCUGUUACAGUAUCAUGUCAGCAUUUAAAUAGCAGUAAAGGUCAUGAAAAGUGAAGUGAAAGGCAGCAAACUCCAUGAAAAACUAAAUACAGUGACAACUGAGGGAAGUGGUAAAGUAAAAAAAUAUUAAUGAUGGAAUUUUAAAGCUGGAAGGGGCAUAGAGACCAUUCUUUUCUCAAUAAUAUUCUGCAAAUAUUAACAGGUGUCAUGUCAGAAACUAAGUUUAGGAAUUGACAAAUUCAAAAAUCUCCCUUACAGCAGGGCUUUGAGAGCCUUUGCUACACUAAAUGCUCUGUGAAUCUAUCUGGUGCUGCGUGGGGGCCUCCAAAUUUAUUUAACCAUAUUUUUUAAUUUGGCAUUUACCUAGAGAAAUGCUAUCACAUUUAAUUCCUUCGUUUUACAGUUUCACCUCCUCAUGUGAUUCCUUCAUUUUGUAAGUGACCGAUUCCACCCUAUACAAUCACAUGGCCAAUGAAUGACAGUCAGAAUUAGAACCUAGUCCCCUGAUUCCCAACCAUGUCUUAUACCAGACUGUUUCCCCUAAUCGAUAGGAAACUACUCCUAAAGGGCAGAAACUGCCUCUCUUUGUUUUUGUCCCCCAACCUCCCCUCCACACAUACACCUCUGUAAUCUGAUGCUUUAAGCUCAGAUUAAAGCAUCAGCAAGCUUUAAUCUGACACAUGGCCGUAGGCUUGAGUUAGCAGUUGGUCCCUUCUUUCUUCCAGACUCUCAUAAGAGUACCCUAUCAGGUCUGGACAGACUUCCGUUUAUGCCUCAGAUUCAAAAUACCCAGGAAAAAGAAGAAGAAAUACAAAACAACAAAAAGAAAAUCAAGAAAAAAAUAAGAUAUCCAGGAAAUAUUUUGUUAGUUUUCUAUUCUGGUGACAAAUGCAAACUUAAGGAAACAAGUUGCACAGUGUUAACUAAUGUUUAACAUUCCUUUCCAUAGUGUUUAUGUGGGCCUUUUAUCAAUUCAUGACAAAUAGGUCACCUCCAAAACUGUUCCAACAUAGGUUAACUCAGAAAUUUAAAAUUUAAGUACUAUCCUUUUUGGAGACUAUGAGAAGAGUUUUUACUAUUGUGUUUUGUUUUGUUUUUUGGUGUGUGUGUGUAUGUAUGUGCAUUCCCCAAAAAUAGUCCAUUGGCAGAUUGUUAGGGUGAACUUUUCCUCUGCCUUUGUGUUUGUAUAAGGGCGGGUGCAUGCUUAGUAUUGUCUGCUACCUUAUGGUUUUUCAUUUAUAUGUAACAUGGUACAACUUGCUUCCUCCCCACCCAACAGUUGUCAGGAUAUGUUGGGGAAUAUUCUUUAGGAAGAUUACAUCUGGUCUUCUGUUGGAGUAAGAUGAAAAACAAGUAUGUUAACACUUGACCUUUACUGCUUUCUCCUGGAAGACAUUGAAUAUCUAGGAGCGUCACUCAUACCUUCCCUUGACUGUACCCACACCCACUGCGGUCCCUGCUUGAUCUCUCAAACUUUUUGUUUCCCUUUGAGCUUCAUGACAAAAAAUUAUAACCAUUUUCUGGUUCUAAGGCUGCCAUAAUCCCAACUUUGCCAGUAAGAAGAUGGAGAAUUUUUGCUCAUAGGGACAUUUCUCAGAAGCAGCUGGCACCAUAACUCUCCUGAGACCCUUGUUUCCUUUCUUUCAGCUCCUAUGACUUCUUAUGUUCACUCUCUCUAACACUACUAAAUGUUGUCAAUGACUGCAAUCACAACUCUUUGAAGGCAGGCUUUUUCUUUUCCUUUGUUACCUCUUAUUUUCAAUAGCCAAAGCAGGUUAGUUUUCUCAGAAUCUUCAGUUUUACUGAAGCAUGCAUUAUUUCUGUUUUCUCUCUGCAGUGAUCAGUUUGGAUGACAGAAACUUUAAACUUUUAUUCUGGCAUUGUCCAGUUCUGAUUUUCUCAGCUGGAACUGGUGCAUGCACAUUUAAUAAUUUCAAAGAAGUGAGAGGUAAAUGUUUUCUCCUGCAUUAUACUGUGUUUCUCUAGCUGAAUUGAUCCGUUUGUUAUCUUGCUCACCCGAAACAAGUAGUUGUGCCCUACAGUGAGCAACCUCAGACUAGGCUGUUCUAAGCAUUCUGGAGAAAAUAAUCCUCAUCAUACAGUUUGUGGUAACUCUUCCAAAAAGUUUAUGAAAAUUGAAAGAUCUCCCUAUGCAUCAGCUGUGGCUGCCACAUUCCGUUCUACUAGGAAGGCUAGUGGCCACAACUCCCUCUAGAACAUCAGAGGAUAAAGUACACUUAUAUAUUAGAAAAGACAGGCAUAUUCUGAUUAUGGUUCAUUCACAAUUUCUCAGUCCAGGGUUCAGUCAGUGACCAUAGCUCUGAGGUCUUCAGGCUAACUCCAAGAACCCGUGCCAGAUAGAAACCUACUCCUACUACCUUUCCACUCACCUUCCCAUUCCCCCACCUUUGCUACCAAAGUGACUUUAAAAGUCGAGUUUUAGGUGUUUGUUUUUUUAACAGUCUAGGAAUUUCAGUGCAAUUCCGUGAGGUGGUGCUGACCUUAGAUGAGAAAUACGUGGCCAGGCUAUAAGGACUACAUGUAGAAUUGAGAUGGGACAGUGUACGUAUGGACUGUGAGGGGAAAGAAAAGGUAAAUGUGUGAAAGGAAAGAGAUUGGUGCAUGGUCAUGACAGUCUGACAGCUUAGACAUUUCAGAGGCAUUGUUUAUGAGAAAGGGGAUAGGGACACAUAGGUCUGAUGACAACCAAAGCCCUUUGAUGAUGCCAUCUGUCACUCAAGGCUCCCCACAGCCUGCCCAACCUGACUCUCCUGCCUGCUUCUCCACUGCCUACCUUCAACAAUCAAACUAUAUUUUUGUUACAGCAAACUACAUUCCAUUUGCCUUUAAAUGCUUGCAUUUUAGUUAUUGUACUGGCUACCUGUUUUUGUCUGCCCAGCAUCCUGUUUCCCCUCCUUUUGGAUCCUCUCCUAGCCAAUUCCAUGUCUUGAAUCCUUUCCUGCUCCUUGUUAAAAUUAUUUUCUGCUUUGUGUGAGUCCCUGUAAGCACCAGCAGCUCAAUCAGCACUGUCUGUACCAUGGUCAAGAGAUGAGUACAUGACUCAGGUCAGACCUUAUUUCCCACCCCAUAAGCCACAAUGAUUAGACAAGAAAUAGGCACAGAACCCUAACUAGAUAGGGCAGAAGCCUUCCAUAGGAUUUUAUUUGCUGGCCCUGAAAUGCAGGUAGCCUUCUAUGGCUGUUAAACACAAUCCAGUGGCACAUGGGGUGAUAUGAGGAUGGAGCCAUCCAUGGCAAAACUCCACCCUUUCCUGUGACAUGGAUUAUGUGCAUCUGCCAUGAAAAGGAAGCAUACACAAGAAAUGAGCCAAGAGUUCCUGGAGAACUGAAGCAAGUAUCACCUCCAGAUCAGUUGUACUUUUAUUUGCUUACACUAUUCUGAGGUGGGUCUCUGUCUCUUGGAUCCAAAAGAGUUCAAAUUAAUAAUCAUUUGACAAAAAAUUACCUCCACAUUCCUAAUGAAGUUGUCUUUGAAGAUAAUGUCUUGUGAUCCCCUGGUUGAAGUUAAUUACUGCUUGUGAGCCCCCAUUAACAACGUGUUCCUUUCCCCAUUGCUUGCUUGUAUCAGCUUUGCUGAAGAUCUAUUGGCUGUAGGUGUGCAGCUUUAUUUCUGUGUUCUCUAUUGUGUUCCAUUGGUCUACGUGUCUGUUAUUGUACCAGUGCCGUGCUGUUUUGGUUACUGUGGUCUUAUAGUUUGAAGCCACAUCUGUGUGAUGCUGCUGGCUUUGUUCUUUCUGCUUUGGGUUGCUUUGGCUAUUCAGGCUCUUUCUUUGGUUCCAUCUGAAUUUUAGAAUAGUUGUUUUCUAAUUCUGUGAAAAUGUUCCAACCUCUGUGAAAAAUGAGGUUGGUAGUUUGAUAGGACAGCAUUGAUUCUGUAAAUUGCUUUGGGCAGUAUGGCCAUUUUUAAACUAUAUUGAUUCUUCCAAUCCAUGAACAUGGAAUGUUUUUCCAUUUUUUGGUUUCAUCCCUGAUUUCUUUCUGCCAUGUUUUGUAGUUCUCCUUGUAGAGAUCUUUCACCUCCUUGGUUAGGUGUAUUUUUAAGUAUUUCAGUUUUUUUAUGGCUAUUGUAAAUGGUAUUGGGUUCUUGAUUUGCUCUCAGCUUGAACGUUAUUGGUGUAUAGAAAUGCUCCUAAUUUUUGUGCAUUGAUUUUGUAUCCUGAAACUUGACUAAAGUUGUUUAUCAGUCUAGGAGCUUUUGGCAGAGUCUUCGGGGUUUUCUAGGUAUAAAAUCAUAUCAGCGAAGAGAGCUAGUUUGAUUUCUUUUCCCAGUUGGAUGCCUUUUAUUUAUUUCUCUUGCCUGAUUGCUCUAAGUUGAAUGGGAGCGAUGAGACUGGGCAUCCUCUUCUUAUUCCAGUUCUCAGAAGGAAUAGUUCCAGCUUUUGCUCAUCCAGUAUGAUGUCUGUGGGUUGGUUGUAGAUGGCUCUUAUUAUUUUGAGAUAUGUUCCUUUGAUACCUAGUCUGUUGAGGGGUUUUAUCAUGAGGGAUGUUGGAUUUUAUCCGUAUUCAAUAAAUGGUGUUGGGAUAACUGGCUAGCCCUAUGCAGAAGAAUGAAACUGGACCCCCCACCUUUCACCGUAUAUGAAAAUUAACUCAAGAUGGAUUAAAGAUUUAAAUGUAAGACCUCAAACUGUAAAAAUCCUAGAAGAAAACCUAGGAAAUACCCUUAUCAACAUCAGCCUUGGCAAAGAACUUUUGGCUAAGUCCCCAAAGGCAAUUGCAACAAAACAGAAAUUGGCAAGUGGGGACCUAAUUAAAGCACUCUGCACAGCAAAAGACACUAUCAACAGAGUAAACAGACAACAUACAGAAUUGGAGAAAAUAUUUGCAAACUAGACAUCCAACAAAGAUCUGACAUCCAGAAUCAAUAAGGAACUUAACAAGCAAAAAACAACCCCAUUAAAAAAUGGGUGAAGGACAUGAACAGACACUUCUCAAAAGAAGACAUACAAGCAAUCAACAAACGUGAAAAAAUGCUCAUCACUAAUCAUCAGAGAAAUGCAAAUCAAAACCACAAUAAGAUACCAUCUCACACCAGUUAGAAUGGCUAUUGUAAAGAAGUCUAAUAACAUGCCAGUAAGGUUUCAGAGAAAAGAGAACAUUUAUACACUGUUGUGGGAAUGUAAAUUAGUUCAGUCACUGUGGAAAGCAGUUUGGAGAUUUCUCAAAUAACUUAAAACAGAUCUACCAUUCAACCCAGCAUAUGGGUUUAUUUCCCAAAAGGAAAUAAAUCCUUCUACCAAAAACACAUAUGGUCAUCACAGUGCUAUUCACAGUAGCAAAGACAGAUCAACGUGGCUGCCCAUCAACAGUGGACUGGAUAAAGAAAAUGUGGUACAUAUAAAUCAUGGAGUAUUAGGCAGCCAUAAAAAGAACAAAAUCAUGUCCUUUGCAGCCAGCCACAUGGAUACAGCUGGAAGCCAUAAUCUAAGCAAAUUAAGAACAGAAAACCAAGUACUGCAUGUUCUAACAAAUGGGAGCUAAAUAUUGAGUACCUCAGGAUGCAAAGGUGGGAACAACAGACACUGCAGACUGGAACACUGUGGGUGAGGAGGGCAGAAGGAUAGGUUGAAAAACUACCUAUUGGGUACUAUGCUCACUACCUGGGUGAUGGGAUCUGUACCUCAAACCUCAGCAUCACACAAUAUACCCUUGUAACAAACUUGCACAUUUACCCACUGUUUCUAAAUGAAAAGUUGAAAUAUUUUUUAUUAAAAAACACAAAAGCAA